AGUGUCUGGGACUGGUGGGCAGAGGCAGCCACCUUAUGGCCUGGACCCGGGUCUGUGCCAGCUGUUGGCGGCAGCUGGCAGAAGCGGUCCUGUUCACCCCCACUGGGAUGGGAGCGGAGGAGAGGACCCCCUUGCUGGGCCCUGCCCCUGCCAGCCAGUCUCCUAGGCCCUCAAUCUUGAGGGGUCCAGGUACCCCAAAUUCUGGGUUCUCCGAUCCCCCUAGCGGCUUUGCCGGCAGUGACCCCCUCUCUAGGGGGCAUAGGGAGGUGGGCCUGAGUGCUGAUAGCAGCUCCCCCUGGGGUCCUGGGGCCACCGGGUUCUCCUGGCCCACAGCCGUCCUUCUGGCCGACCUUGAGCGGGAUGCCAGGCAGGGGGAGUGUGCCCUUCCUGGGGCUGCCAUGGCAGGCCUGGCCCCACUGAAACCCGAAGCCAGCCGGAGCUCCAGCCCCGGGCCGACUGGCUGCAUUAGGGCAAGGGUAGCGGCAGAGGCUGGAACAAGGAACCCGGGCAAUGCUGGGGCUGAGCUGGAGAGCUGGCUGCCUUGCUGCCACGGCCAUCCUGAGACUCCAGAGCCGAGGGGAGGGCAGCUGCCAACUGCACCAGAGCUGCCAUCAGUCAUGCUCUUAAACGGGGACUGCCCAGAGAGCCUGAAGAAGGAGGCGGCGGCGGCCGAGCCACCCAGGGAAAAUGGGCUUGACGAGGCCGGCCCGGGAGAUGAGACCACCGGCCAGGAAGUCAUUGUCAUUCAGGACACGGGCUUUUCUGUGAAGAUCCUCGCCCCUGGGAUCGAGCCCUUCUCCCUGCAGGUGUCCCCCCAGGAGAUGGUGCAGGAGAUUCACCAGGUGCUCAUGGACCGGGAGGACACGUGUCACCGCACCUGCUUCUCACUGCACCUGGAUGGCAACGUGCUGGACCACUUCUCGGAGCUGCGCAGCGUCGAGGGGCUGCAGGAGGGCUCUGUGCUGCGUGUGGUGGAAGAGCCGUACACGGUGCGUGAGGCCCGCAUCCACGUGCGCCAUGUCCGAGACCUGCUCAAGAGCCUGGACCCAUCCGAUGCCUUCAACGGGGUUGACUGCAACUCCUUGUCCUUCCUGAGUGUCUUCACCGACGGCGACCUGGGAGACAGCGGGAAGCGGAAGAAGGGCUUGGAGAUGGACCCCAUCGACUGCACACCACCCGAGUACAUCCUGCCAGGGAGCCGGGAGCGGCCACUGUGUCCCCUGCAGCCCCAAAACCGUGACUGGAAGCCCUUGCAGUGCCUGAAAGUACUCACCAUGAGCGGAUGGAACCCGCCCCCGGGGAACCGGAAGAUGCACGGGGACCUCAUGUACCUGUUUGUGAUCACAGCCGAGGACCGGCAAGUCAGCAUCACCGCGUCCACACGGGGCUUUUACCUGAAUCAGUCCACAGCUUAUCACUUCAACCCCAAGCCCGCCAGCCCCCGCUUCCUAAGCCAUUCCCUAGUGGAGCUGCUCAACCAGAUCAGCCCGACCUUCAAGAAGAACUUCGCUGUGCUGCAGAAGAAAAGGGUCCAGCGCCACCCGUUCGAGAGGAUCGCCACCCCAUUCCAGGUGUACAGCUGGACAGCCCCCCAGGCGGAGCAUGCCAUGGAUUGCGUGCGUGCAGAGGACGCCUACACCUCGAGGCUGGGCUAUGAGGAGCACAUUCCUGGACAGACCCGAGACUGGAAUGAGGAGCUGCAGACGACGAGGGAGCUGCCUCGCAAGAACCUGCCUGAGCGGCUGCUCCGAGAAAGGGCCAUAUUCAAGGUGCACAGCGACUUCACCGCGGCAGCCACCAGGGGCGCCAUGGCCGUCAUUGACGGCAACGUGAUGGCCAUCAACCCCAGCGAGGAGACCAAGAUGCAGAUGUUCAUCUGGAACAACAUCUUCUUCAGCCUGGGCUUCGACGUCCGAGACCACUACAAGGACUUCGGGGGGGACGUGGCGGCCUACGUGGCGCCCACCAACGACCUGAAUGGCGUCCGCACGUACAACGCGGUGGACGUGGAGGGGCUGUACACGCUGGGCACGGUGGUGGUGGAUUACCGCGGCUACCGGGUCACGGCCCAGUCCAUCAUCCCCGGCAUCCUGGAGCGGGACCAGGAGCAGAGCGUCAUCUACGGCUCCAUCGACUUCGGCAAGACCGUGGUGUCACACCCGCGGUACCUGGAGCUGCUGGAGCGCACGAGUCGGCCCCUCAAGAUCCUGCGGCACCAGGUGCUCAACGACCGUGACGAGGAGGUGGAGCUCUGCUCCUCGGUCGAGUGCAAGGGCAUCAUUGGCAACGACGGGCGCCACUACAUCCUCGACCUGCUGCGCACCUUCCCCCCGGACCUCAACUUCCUGCCCGUGCCUGGCGAGGAGCUGCCUGAGGAAUGCGCCCGCGCCGGCUUCCCCCGCGCCCACCGGCACAAGCUCUGCUGCCUGCGCCAGGAGCUGGUGGACGCCUUCGUGGAGCACAGGUACCUCCUCUUUAUGAAGCUGGCCGCCUUGCAGCUGAUGCAGCAGAACGCCAGCCAGCUGGAGACCCCCUCCUCCCUGGAAAAUGGUGGUCCUUCCUCCUUGGAGUCCAAGUCUGAGGAUCCUCCAGGACAGGAGGCGGGAAGUGAGGAGGAGGGUAGCAGCGCCAGCGGCCUGGCCAAGGUGAAGGAGCUGGCAGAGACCAUCGCCGCAGACGACGGCACAGCAGACCCUCGGAGCCGGGAGGUGAUCCGCAACGCGUGCAAGGCGGUCGGCUCCAUCAGCAGCACCGCCUUCGACAUUCGCUUCAAUCCUGACAUCUUCUCACCAGGGGUUCGUUUCCCUGAGUCCUGCCAGGAUGAAGUUCGGGACCAGAAGCAGCUGCUGAAGGACGCGGCUGCCUUCCUGCUCUCCUGCCAGAUCCCUGGCUUGGUGAAGGACUGCAUGGAGCACGCGGUCCUGCCCGUGGACGGGGCAACGCUGGCAGAGGUGAUGCGCCAGCGGGGCAUCAACAUGCGCUACCUGGGCAAGGUGCUGGAGCUGGUGCUGCGGAGCCCGGCCCGCCACCAGCUGGACCACGUCUUUAAAAUCGGCAUUGGAGAACUCAUCACCCGCUCGGCCAAGCACAUCUUCAAGACGUACUUACAGGGAGUCGAGCUCUCCGGCCUCUCAGCCGCCAUCAGCCACUUCCUGAACUGCUUCCUGAGCUCCUACCCAAACCCCGUGGCCCACCUGCCCGCCGACGAGCUGGUCUCCAAGAAGCGGAAUAAGAGGAGGAAAAACCGGCCCCCGGGGGCUGCAGAUAACACAGCCUGGGCUGUCAUGACCCCCCAGGAGCUCUGGAAGAACAUCUGCCAGGAGGCCAAGAACUACUUUGACUUCGACCUCGAGUGUGAGACCGUGGACCAGGCUGUGGAGACCUACGGCCUGCAGAAGAUAACGCUCCUGCGGGAGAUCUCGCUGAAAACAGGGAUCCAGGUCCUGCUGAAGGAGUACAGCUUCGACAGUCGCCACAAGCCCGCGUUCACCGAGGAGGACGUGCUCAACAUCUUCCCCGUGGUCAAGCACGUCAACCCCAAGGCCUCGGAUGCCUUCCAUUUCUUCCAGAGCGGGCAGGCCAAAGUGCAGCAGGGCUUCCUGAAGGAGGGCUGUGAGCUCAUCAAUGAGGCCCUGAACCUGUUUAACAACGUCUACGGAGCCAUGCACGUGGAGACCUGCGCCUGCCUGCGCCUCCUCGCCCGCCUCCACUACAUCAUGGGCGACUACGCAGAGGCCCUGAGUAACCAGCAGAAGGCGGUGCUGAUGAGCGAGCGGGUGAUGGGCACCGAGCACCCCAACACCAUCCAGGAAUACAUGCACCUGGCCCUGUACUGCUUCGCCAGCAGCCAGCUGUCCACCGCCCUGAGCCUGCUGUACCGCGCCCGCUACCUCAUGCUGCUGGUGUUCGGGGAAGACCACCCCGAGAUGGCGCUGCUGGACAACAACAUCGGGCUGGUGCUGCACGGGGUGAUGGAGUACGACCUGUCGCUGCGCUUCCUGGAGAACGCGCUGGCCGUCAGCACCAAGUACCACGGGCCCAAGGCCCUCAAGGUGGCCCUCAGCCACCACCUUGUCGCCCGAGUCUACGAGAGCAAAGCUGAGUUCCGGUCGGCCCUGCAGCACGAGAAGGAGGGUUACACCAUCUACAAGACGCAGCUGGGCGAGGACCAUGAGAAGACCAAGGAAAGCUCCGAGUACCUCAAGUGCCUGACCCAGCAGGCCGUGGCCCUGCAGCGCACCAUGAACGAGAUCUACCGCAACGGCUCCAGCGCCAACAUCCCGCCCCUCAAGUUCACGGCCCCCAGCAUGGCCAGCGUCUUGGAGCAGCUGAACGUCAUUAACGGCAUCCUCUUCAUUCCUCUCAGCCAAAAAGACCUGGAGAAUCUGAAAGCCGAGGUGGCGCGGCGGCACCAGCUCCAGGAGGCCAGCAGAAACAGGGAUAGAGCCGAGGAGCCCAUGGCUACCGAGCCCGCGCCAGCGGGGGCCCCAGGAGACCUGGGCUCCCAGCCCCCGGCUGCCAAGGACCCUUCUCCGAGCGUGCAGGGAUAGAGAGGGAGCCAGACGGACAGCCAGCCAGCGGCCCCGUCACCAGGGAGCCCGACUGCGGGAGAAGGGGGCGAGCCUGCGGGCGGAAGAGGAAGCAAGGCCCUCUUCCUCCACGUCUCACCCCACCCCACCCCCGUGUCCUCCUGGGAGCCUGGCCUGCCUGCCCCGCAGAAGGUGUUUUUGCGCUGGUUCAAUGAAUAGAUGAUGCAGAGGCCCCAUUGGAGACACGUGAAUGGCGUGUGCGGCCAUCAGUUCCCGGCUGGGGGGCAGGUGUUGCUUCGGCCCCCGCCGUCCGGCCGGCGUGUGCGAGUGCGCCCCUGGCUGUGAGUGUUGACCGUUCCUCUCCCCUGUACAUAGCCCGAGCCAGUCCUGAGUGGGUGACUCCUGAGUGGGUGACGCGCAGACGGGAUUUCUCAGGUCAUUUGUAUGGUCGACAUGAUGGCUGCUGCUUUGGCUGCCACCACCCCCGGGCCCAGCCUGUCUGAAAGUUCAGGGUUUAGGCCGAAAAACCCGGUGGGGAGGGGUGGGGAGCCGGAGCUCUGUGGCGGGGCUGGAGGGCUGGGGUGCACUUUAGUUUGGGGCGGGACGGGAGCCGCCGUUGUGACUGGCGUGGUCUGGCUGCUGCUCCCGAACGGAGGGGUCGGGGUUGGCUUGCUGGGCCCUCAGAGCCCAGUGGGUGGCUCUGACUCGGCUCCCUACUCCCUGCACCCAGCUGGGCGCAGCCUUGGGGCCUGCGGUCUGAAUGUAUCCCUCCCCUCAGUUUUAACCUGAGCUGCCGAACGCACAGUGGGCCGGGGGCGAGGCUGGGGGAAGCGGGGCCCAAUUACGGAUCCCGGGAGUUACAGGUGCCGACGUGAUGUCGCUUCUCUGGUGCCCAGCUCCCUUCCUGGUCUGAGACUAGCUCUGGGGGUGGCGGGGGCCCCCACACGCUGCUCCCGCUCCACCCUGCCCGUGCUGCUGCUCUGUGCCUGCUGUCAGAGCCCUGGUGGGGGAGGAUGUGGCCACCCUGAGACCCGGAGGAGACGGGCGUCUGCCUGGGUUUGCGGAGAGCCGCUUAUGGGUGUGGUCCGUCCAGACACCUUGUUUCAAGGGGGAUGGGCGUGAGCGGGCAAGCAGAGCAUCCCCACCGCUGAGCAAGAACUUUUUCUUGUUUUUAAACCAUCACGUCCUCAUUUCACAUUGGAAUAAAGUGAGUUUUUGAAACCUGCGG